GACCAUUUCCUACACAAGCUCAUUCAGAGGAGGAUGAAGACCAUUUUGGAGGAAGAAAAGCACCCUUAUUAAGAAUUGCAGCAAGUAAGCCAACAAGGUCUUUUCAGGAUGAUUUUCUUAUAUCAAGUGGUACAUUUCAUUUUAUUUACUUCAGUUUCUGGUGAAUGUGUGACUCAGUUGUUGAAGGACACCUGCUUUGAAGGAGGGGACAUUACUACGGUCUUCACACCAAGCGCCAAGUACUGCCAGGUAGUCUGCACUUACCACCCAAGAUGUUUACUCUUCACUUUCACGGCGGAAUCACCAUCUGAGGAUCCCACCCGAUGGUUUACUUGUGUCCUGAAAGACAGUGUUACAGAAACACUGCCAAGAGUGAAUAGGACAGCAGCGAUUUCUGGGUAUUCUUUCAAGCAAUGCUCACACCAAAUAAGCGCUUGCAACAAAGACAUUUAUGUGGACCUAGACAUGAAGGGCAUAAACUAUAACAGCUCAGUUGCCAAGAGUGCUCAAGAAUGCCAAGAAAGAUGCACGGAUGACGUCCACUGCCACUUUUUCACGUACGCCACAAGGCAGUUUCCCAGCCUGGAGCAUCGUAACAUUUGUCUACUGAAGCACACCCAAACAGGGACACCAACCAGAAUAACGAAGCUCGAUAAAGUGGUGUCUGGAUUUUCACUGAAAUCCUGUGCACUUUCUAAUCUGGCUUGUAUUAGGGACAUUUUCCCUAAUACGGUGUUUGCAGACAGCAACAUCGACAGUGUCAUGGCUCCCGAUGCUUUUGUCUGUGGCCGAAUCUGCACUCAUCAUCCCGGUUGCUUGUUUUUUACCUUCUUUUCCCAGGAAUGGCCCAAAGAAUCUCAAAGAAAUCUUUGUCUCCUUAAAACAUCUGAGAGUGGAUUGCCCAGUACACGCAUUAAAAAGAGCAAAGCUCUUUCUGGUUUCAGUCUACAAAGCUGCAGGCACAGCAUCCCAGUGUUCUGCCAUUCUUCAUUUUACCAUGACACUGAUUUCUUGGGAGAAGAACUGGAUAUUGUUGCUGCAAAAAGUCACGAGGCCUGCCAGAAACUGUGCACCAAUGCCGUCCGCUGCCAGUUUUUUACCUAUACCCCAGCCCAAGCAUCCUGCAACGAAGGGAACAGGGGCAAGUGUUACUUAAAGCUUUCUUCAAACGGAUCUCCAACUAAAAUACUUCACGGGAGAGGAGGCAUCUCUGGAUACACAUUAAGGUUGUGUAAAAUGGAUAAUGAGUGUACCACCAAAAUCAAGCCCAGGAUCGUUGGAGGAACUGCGUCUGUUCGUGGUGAGUGGCCGUGGCAGGUGACCCUGCACACAACCUCACCCACUCAGAGACACCUGUGUGGAGGCUCCAUCAUUGGAAACCAGUGGAUAUUAACAGCCGCUCACUGUUUCUAUGGGGUAGAGUCACCUAAGAUUUUGCGUGUCUACAGUGGCAUUUUAAAUCAAUCUGAAAUAAAAGAGGACACAUCUUUCUUUGGGGUUCAAGAAAUAAUAAUCCAUGAUCAGUAUAAAAUGGCAGAAAGCGGGUAUGAUAUUGCCUUGUUGAAACUGGAAACCACAGUGAAUUACACAGAUUCUCAACGACCCAUAUGCCUGCCUUCCAAAGGAGAUAGAAAUGUAAUAUACACUGAUUGCUGGGUGACUGGAUGGGGGUACAGAAAACUAAGAGACAAAAUACAAAAUACUCUCCAGAAAGCCAAGAUACCCUUAGUGACCAACGAAGAGUGCCAGAAGAGAUACAGAGGACAUAAAAUAACCCAUAAGAUGAUCUGUGCCGGCUACAGGGAAGGAGGGAAGGACGCUUGCAAGGGAGAUUCGGGAGGCCCUCUGUCCUGCAAACACAAUGAGGUCUGGCAUCUGGUAGGCAUCACGAGCUGGGGCGAAGGCUGUGCUCAAAGGGAGCGGCCAGGUGUUUACACCAACGUGGUCGAGUACGUGGACUGGAUUCUGGAGAAAACUCAAGCAGUGUGAAUGGGUUCCCAGGGGCCAUUGGAGUCCCUGAAGGACCCAGGAUUUGCUGGGAGAGGGUGUUGAGUUCACUGUGCCAGCAUGCUUCCUCCACAGUAACACGCUGAAGGGGCUUGGUGUUUGUAAGAAAAUGCUAGAAGAAAACAAACUGUCACAAGUUGUUAUGUCCAAAACUCCCGUUCUAUGAUCGUUGUAGUUUGUUUGAGCAUUCAGUCUCUUUGUUUUUGAUCACGCUUCUAUGGAGUCCAAGAAUUACCAUAAGGCAAUAUUUCUGAAGAUUACUAUAUAGGCAGAUAUAGCAGAAAAUAACCAAGUAGUGGCAGUGGGGAUCAGGCAGAAGAACUGGUAAAAGAAGCCACCAUAAAUAGAUUUGUUCGAUGAAAGAUGAAAACUGGAAGAAAGGAGAACAAAGACAGUCUUCACCAUUUUGCAGGAAUCUACACUCUGCCUAUGUGAACACAUUUCUUUUGUAAAGAAAGAAAUUGAUUGCAUUUAAUGGCAGAUUUUCAGAAUAGUCAGGAAUUCUUGUCAUUUCCAUUUUAAAAUAUAUAUUAAAAAAAAUCAGUUCGAGUAGACACGAGCUAAGAGUGAAUGUGAAGAUAACAGAAUUUCUGUGUGGAAGAGGAUUACAAGCAGCAAUUUACCUGGAAGUGAUACCUUAGGGGCAAUCUUGAAGAUACACUUUCCUGAAAAAUGAUUUGUGAUGGAUUGUAUAUUUAUUUAAAAUAUCUUGGGAGGGGAGGCUGAUGGAGAUAGGGAGCAUGCUCAAACCUCCCUAAGACAAGCUGCUGCUGUGACUAUGGGCUCCCAAAGAGCUAGAUCGUAUAUUUAUUUGACAAAAAUCACCAUAGACUGCAUCCAUACUACAGAGAAAAAACAAUUAGGGCGCAAAUGGAUAGUUACAGUAAAGUCUUCAGCAAGCAGCUGCCUGUAUUCUAAGCACUGGGAUUUUCUGUUUCGUGCAAAUAUUUAUCUCAUUAUUGUUGUGAUCUAGUUCAAUAACCUAGAAUUUGAAUUGUCACCACAUAGCUUUCAAUCUGUGCCAACAACUAUACAAUUCAUCAAGUGUG